GCAGAGGUCACCGUCCAGGUUGGACAGCAGCACCUUUGAGCGAUGGCGGCGUCUGGGGAACCCCAGAGGCAGUGGCAAGAGGAGGUGGCGGCGGUGGUAGUGGUGGGCUCCUGCAUGACCGACCUGGUCAGGAGGAUGUGCAUGAGGAUAUGUUAUGUGCACUUUUGUUGCCAGCCCACACCACAGCUGCAGAACUGUUCAAGUCUUUGCGUGAUUACAUGUCAGGAAAACUGAACUGGUCAUUUUGUGUGAGUAUAUGCAUGGACAGAGUGGCUGCCAUGGCUGGACAGCUUCUGGUUUCACUACUCACAUCAAAGAGGUUGCUUCUGAAUGUGAGUCUACACACCAUGUCAUCCAUAGAGAAAUGCUGGCUAGCCAAAAAAUGUCACCUGAACUUAACAGCAUUUUGCAGGAUGUGAUUAAAAUUAUCAACCACGUUAAAGUACAUGCCCUUAACUCACGUCUCUUCGCACAGCUCUGUGAGGAGGUGGGUGCAGUGCACACAUGUCUUCUCUCACACACACAAGUGAGAUGGCUUUCUAAAGGUAGAUCACUGAUCAGAGUUUUUGAGUUACAAGAGCCACUCCGGAGAUUUCUUUUAGAAAAACAGUCACCACUGGCAGCACAUUUCAGUGACACAGAAUGGGUUGCAAACCUGGCUUCCUUGUGUGACAUAUUCAACCUGCUCAACGAACUCGAUCUGUCACUUCAGGGGAGAAUGACAACUGUGUUCAAAUUGUCAGAUAAAGGGGCUGCAUUCAAAGCCAAACUGGAAUUAUGGGGGUGACAAGUGAACAUGGGGAUUUCUGACAUGUUUCAAACAUUAGCAGAUAUUUUGAAAGAGACUGAACCAGGGCCUUCUUUCCCCCAGCUGGUGCAUGAUCACCUAUCUCAGCUUUUAAAGGAGUUUGAGCAUUACUUCCCAACCACAAAAGACCCCCCAGACUGGGAAGGAAUGGAUCUGCAACCCAUUUGUGGAUAAGCCAAGGUGAAUCGACUUUGUCCGUGCUGGAAAAGGACCAACUGCUUGAGAUCGCAAAUGACGGUGGCCUUAAAAGUAUGUUGAAACAGCUUCAAAUCUUCACACAGUCCGGAUUGAAGUCAAGGCAUAAUAUCCAGAGACUGCCCCAAAAGCACUGAAAAGCUUGCUUCCAUUUCCAACACCCUAUCUUUGUGAAGCAGAGUUUUCUGCAGUAACAGCAACCAAAACGAGAUUAUGGAGUAGACUGGACAUAAACAACACACUUCAGUCUUACUUCUCGUUUGCCAAAAACUGGAGAAACCAUCCAUGGACAUAAGUUUUUUAUUGGCUUUGGAGGGAAAGGUGCCAACCAGUGUGUCCAAGCUGCUCGGCUUGGAGCAAUGACGUCCAUGGUGUGUAAGGUUGGCAAAGAUUCUUUUGGCAAUGAUUAUAUAGAAAACUUAAAACAGAAUGAUAUUUCUACAGAAUUUACAUAUCAGACUAAAGAUGCUGCUACAGGAACUGCUUCUAUAAUUGUCAAUAAUGAAGGCCAGAAUAUCAUUGUCAUAGUGGCUGGAGCAAAUUUACUUUUGAAUACGGAGGAUCUGAGGGCAGCAGCCAAUGUCAUUAGCAGAGCCAAAGUCAUGGUCUGCCAGCUCGAAAUAACUCCAGCAACUUCUUUGGAAGCCCUAACAAUGGCCCGCAGGAGUGGAGUGAAAACCUUGUUCAAUCCAGCCCCUGCCAUUGCUGACCUGGAUCCCCAGUUCUACACCCUCUCAGAUGUGUUCUGCUGCAAUGAAAGUGAGGCUGAGAUUUUAACUGGCCUCACGGUGGGCAGCGCUGCAGAUGCUGGGGAGGCUGCAUUAGUGCUCUUGAAAAGGGGCUGCCAGGUGGUAAUCAUUACCUUAGGGGCUGAAGGAUGUGUGGUGCUGUCACAGACAGAACCUGAGCCAAAGCACAUUCCCACAGAGAAAGUCAAGGCUGUGGAUACCACGGGUGCUGGUGACAGCUUUGUGGGAGCUCUGGCCUUCUACCUGGCUUACUAUCCAAAUCUGUCCUUGGAAGACAUGCUCAACAGAUCCAAUUUCAUUGCAGCAGUCAGUGUCCAGGCUGCAGGAACACAGUCAUCUUACCCUUACAAAAAAGACCUUCCGCUUACUCUGUUUUGAUUGCUAUUAGUCCCAAAAUAAAUAUACCUGGGAAUAAAAUGUACUUGGGGGUGGCUGCUCCUGGCUAAUGCUUAUUAGAAAAUGUCCUCGUCCCCUUUCUUUGCAAAUAUUAGUUCUUUUACGAAGUCAUCCUCAAGCUUCAAUUUAUUUAUAACGAUGAUUCUUUUGCUUUCCAUGCAUUUGCACAAAACAACCAGAAUUAAAGAUUCCACAACCAAGAUCUGUACAAACAUAAA